ACAGUUGGUCCGAGCUGCCGAAAGGUCUGGUCGCAGAGACAGGAACGUGUAAUCCUCAGCGUGCUCCAGCCCACAGCUUCGCUCUACUGCUCGGCAGGGCAGCUGGCCUCUGGGCACCGGCGGCCCCUCUGCCUCGCGGAAAAGCCUGAUGAAGUCCUCCGAUAUUGAUCAGGAUUUAUUCACAGACAGUUACUGCAAGGUGUGCAGUGCACAGCUGAUCUCCGAAUCGCAGCGUGUGGCCCACUACGAGAGUCGAAAACAUGCAAGCAAAGUCCGACUGUAUUACAUGCUUCACCCCAGGGAUGGAGGGUGUCCUGCCAAGAGGCUCCGGUCAGAAAAUGGAAGUGAUGCCGACAUGGUGGAUAAGAACAAGUGCUGCACACUCUGCAACAUGUCAUUCACUUCAGCGGUGGUGGCCGAUUCCCAUUAUCAAGGCAAAAUCCACGCCAAGAGGUUAAAACUCUUGCUAGGAGAGAAGACCCCAUUAAAGACCACAGCAACACCCCUGAGCCCACUUAAGCCCCCACGGAUGGACACUGCUCCGGUGGUCGCAUCUCCCUAUCAAAGAAGAGAUUCAGACAGAUACUGUGGGCUCUGUGCAGCCUGGUUUAAUAACCCUCUGAUGGCCCAGCAACAUUAUGAUGGCAAGAAACACAAAAAGAAUGCGGCAAGAGUUGCUUUGUUAGAACAACUGGGGACAACCCUGGAUAUGGGGGAACUGAGAGGCAAAGCAUGCUUCAGUAUGAGACAUCUCCUCCACAAUGGAAAGAUGAGAACAGUUACUGAAGAUCAUCUGUGGUUACUCAUAGUUAGGCAUAGUUCCCGGCUUUCUUUGUUCUUCAUUGCCACCGUGGAAACAAAAGGCAGAUGAAAGCUUCUCGACUGCUUGGGAUCAGUUCUUAUCUAGUGUGUGGGCACAGACAUGUGCUUGGUUAAACACACUGGGAAGGCAGCCAUGGAGAAAUGUACAGGAAUUCUAAAGCUGCGAAGGAAUUUACACCUGCACCUCAUAGCUCAGAAUAGAACAUGGCCUCCAUGGUAUCUUCAAAUUCCAAAACUUCUCCAGUUUCAUCCCAAGAGUUAUACACUCAUGAAGAAUCUGACACAGGAACAAGUAGAUAAGGUUUGACUUUGCCUCCUCAUACCCUUUUUUUACUCAGAGAAAACUUUGGUAUCUUUUAAAUAUCUUCCCUAGGGAAACUGGGACAGUCAUUUUGGUCUCAUGAAAUAUGGCUUAUAUGUGAGGUUUCCAGAGCUGCUAGAAUGGAAAUGAUCUCUGCUCCUUCUGAGCAUAUGCACGGCAGUGCUCCUCCUCUAAAUCUGGUAGUAUAUUGUACACAUUCCCUCCAAUCCUCUUGACUUAGCUCACAUAUCCUGGGGAUGGAGAAAUGGAGAGAAUAUUAAUAGCCCUCCUCUAGCAGAUAGCUUUUCUAGGGAAGAGGCUAAACUUGCCACAACUUUGCCAGGUUGUUCUUAUGAAGGAAGAACAUACCUGUGUAUUAGGUUUGAAAACAAUCUUUACCUUGGUACUAGAUAGAGUUAAUGAUAUAUUGUCUUAAAGGGAUGACCCUAUUUGACCCAGUGAGAAAACUGGGACAGCCAAAUGGUCUGAAGUAUUUGGCUUCUCUAGUCUCCUGAUAGCCACAUUGACUGUGUAUGUGUGAUGUCCCUCUCAGCCACAAUGAUUAGGAAGACUAAAUGUUUAAUUAUUUUUCCUACUCUUUGCCCUUGAUAACCUAGCAUAACUUUUGUUGGAUACCCUAUAUUAUUGAAUGUUCACCCGCUAGAACAGUGCGCCAUUUGGUGCAGGUAUGAAUUUUUUUAUGGCCUCUAAGUUUAACAGAUAAAGUACCAGAUGACUAAUUGAAUUUGAAUUUCAGAUAACAACUCUUUUAACCUGCGUACAAUAAGUAUGCAGGUAUUUGGGACAUACUUAUACUAAAAAUCUGUUUGUUAUUUAUCCAAAAUUCAAAUUUAAUUGAGCAUCCUGUAUUUUUAUUUGGUAAAUUUGACAACCUUAAUGACCUGCCAACUUUUUCAGGUUUAAAUAUCUUUAAAAGUUUAAAUUUCAAUCAAAUAAAGAGUAUAAGGCCAUUUUAGAGAGAGGAAAUGAGUUCACUUUAUUUUUAUUUAUUUUAUUAUUAUCAUUAUUUUAGACGGAUUCUCGCUUUGUUGCCCAGGCUGCUUGUUCAUGAUCCCAACAUUUGUAAAGUCAUUUAAAAAAAGAAUAACUGAAACCUUAUAUCCUUUGACUAAUAAAUCCUAGAGAUCUAAUAGGCAGAGUGCCUAAACUUAAAAAUACUGUAUUGUAUACUUAAAAAUACUGUAUUGUAUACUUAAAAAUUUGCUAAGAAGGCAGAUCUUAUGUUAAGUGCUUUUAUCACAAUUAAAAUAAUAAGAAUAAAAAAAGAGGGCAGAGGAAACACAGAGGUGAUGAAUGGGUAAGAGCACAGAUUGUGAUGAUGGUUUCAAAGGUGUACAUUUAUCUCCAAAUGCAUCAAGUUGUGUACAUGAAAUAUUUAUAGCUUUUAGUAUGCCAAUCCUACUUCAAUACAGUAGCUUAAAAAAUAAAAGAAUAAAAUCACUAAAACACUGUUUUUUAGAAUAAUUCUUUUCUGUACAAAUUCUUGAGAUGUUUAAAGUGUGCAAAAAAAUCUGAGCUUUUCUUUCAUUCCCAUUUGUCUAACAAGAUUUGGAAAGUCACCUAACCAAAAUAAAUGUAAAUGUUUUUUCCACA